UGCCCUCUCACACAUGCCCGGGCUAUGUCAUCUGCUCGUGUUCCUAGUUAUCUGUGUGCAUCUGCUUUUCAAGAAAAUGUAAAAACUGUGCUACACAUGGAAAUAUGUUUAGGUGGAUAAAUAAUGCACACCUGCAUACGUUUCCAUAGGGGCCUUAAGGAUGGGACCAAAAACGUUUGGCAGGAGACGGCCACUCUCAUGUGGUACAUACCAUGUAGUUCGUGUUCCUAUGUUCACAUGAUGCAGGCUUCAUGCGUUACACCUAAGUUCUAGGUGGUUUUUCUGGCUAUGUGUGUCUGUGAAGCGGAACUAUGGAGCACUGCUGAUGCGGAUCCGUGGCCGUUCACAUGGUUUCAAGGCACAAUGAGACUCACUGGCCCUUGGAAACUUUGGCUUUGGAUGUCAAUAUUUCUGCUUCCUGCUUCCACUUCCGUGACCGUUAGGGACAAGACAGAAGAGUCAUGCCCUAUCCUGAGAAUAGAGGGACAUCAGCUGACAUAUGACAACAUAAACAAACUUGAAGUUUCAGGUUUUGAUCUAGGAGACAGCUUUUCUCUAAGACGUGCAUUUUGUGAAAGUGAUAAAACCUGUUUCAAAUUGGGAAGUGCACUUCUUAUUAGAGACACUAUUAAGAUAUUUCCCAAAGGCCUUCCUGAGGAGUACUCAGUAGCUGCCAUGUUUCGAGUACGAAGAAACGCCAAAAAGGAACGGUGGUUUCUGUGGCAGGUUUUAAACCAGCAGAAUAUUCCACAGAUUUCUAUAGUAGUUGAUGGUGGAAAGAAGGUGGUGGAAUUUAUGUUUCAAGCCACAGAGGGAGAUGUGUUGAACUACAUUUUUAGAAAUCGAGAACUCCGUCCUUUGUUUGAUCGUCAGUGGCACAAACUUGGCAUUAGUAUACAAUCCCAGGUCAUUUCACUUUAUAUGGAUUGUAAUUUAAUUGCGAGGAGGCAGACUGAUGAAAAGGACACUGUGGAUUUCCAUGGACGGACAGUUAUUGCUACGCGAGCUUCAGAUGGCAAGCCUGUGGAUAUUGAACUUCACCAACUUAAAAUCUACUGCAGUGCAAACCUCAUAGCUCAAGAAACAUGUUGUGAAAUAUCAGAUACUAAGUGCCCAGAGCAGGAUGGCUUUGGAAAUAUUGCAUCAUCAUGGGUAACUGCUCAUGCCAGUAAAAUGUCUUCAUAUCUGCCAGCAAAGCAGGAACUUAAAGACCAGUGCCAGUGCAUUCCAAACAAGGGAGAAGCAGGAUUACCAGGAGCUCCGGGUUCACCUGGGCAGAAAGGGCAUAAAGGAGAGCCGGGUGAAAAUGGUUUACAUGGUGCUCCAGGAUUCCCUGGUCAAAAGGGAGAGCAAGGUUUUGAAGGCAGCAAAGGAGAAACUGGUGAAAAGGGUGAACAAGGAGAAAAAGGAGAUCCAGCUCUGGCUGGCCUUAAUGGAGAAAAUGGUUUGAAAGGUGACUUGGGUCCUCAUGGUCCACCUGGCCCAAAAGGAGAAAAGGGAGAUACAGGACCCCCAGGACCACCAGCCUUACCUGGUUCCCUGGGGAUACAAGGCCCCCAAGGUCCACCUGGAAAAGAGGGUCAGAGGGGAAGACGAGGGAAAACAGGACCUCCCGGAAAACCAGGACCCCCAGGACCACCUGGACCUCCUGGAAUACAAGGAAUACACCAAACUCUUGGUGGAUAUUAUAACAAGGAUAACAAGGGAAAUGAUGAACAUGAAGCUGGAGGCCUGAAAGGAGACAAGGGUGAAACUGGACUACCAGGAUUUCCAGGGUCUGUUGGCCCUAAAGGACAAAAAGGAGAACCUGGAGAGCCUUUUACAAAAGGAGAAAAAGGAGAUAGAGGAGAACCUGGGGUAAUAGGAUCACAGGGAGUAAAGGGUGAACCUGGAGAUCCCGGACCCCCUGGUUUAAUAGGAAGCCCAGGACUAAAGGGUCAGCAAGGAUCUGCAGGCUCCAUGGGACCCAGAGGACCGCCAGGAGAUGUUGGAUUGCCAGGAGAACAUGGUAUCCCAGGAAAACAAGGCAUUAAAGGAGAAAAGGGAGAUCCGGGUGGGAUCAUAGGCCCUCCCGGGCUUCCAGGUCCAAAAGGUGAGGCUGGUCCUCCAGGGAAAAGCCUGCCAGGGGAACCAGGAUUAGAUGGAAAUCCUGGAGCACCUGGUCCACGUGGGCCAAAGGGUGAAAGAGGACUUCCAGGUGUUCACGGUUCCCCAGGGGACAUAGGCCCACAAGGGAUAGGAAUUCCUGGCAGAACAGGCGCCCAAGGACCAGCUGGAGAGCCAGGUAUUCAGGGUCCUCGAGGUCUCCCUGGGUUGCCAGGAACUCCAGGGACUCCAGGGAAUGAUGGAGUUCCAGGGAGAGAUGGAAAGCCAGGCCUGCCAGGCCCCCCAGGUGACCCGAUUGCACUUCCUCUCUUGGGAGACAUCGGUGCUUUGCUCAAGAAUUUCUGUGGCAACUGCCAAGCCAGUGUCCCAGGGCUGAAAAGCAACAAAGGAGAAGAAGGAGGUGCUGGUGAGCCUGGAAAGUAUGAUUCCAUGGCCCGGAAGGGUGAUAUAGGGCCACGGGGUCCUCCAGGAAUCCCAGGAAGAGAGGGACCAAAGGGAAGCAAAGGAGAGCGGGGCUACCCUGGGAUACCUGGGGAGAAAGGCGAUGAGGGUCUUCAAGGAAUUCCAGGCAUUCCAGGUGCUCCAGGCCCGACUGGACCCCCUGGCUUAAUGGGAAGAACUGGACAUCCUGGUCCCACAGGAGCAAAAGGUGAAAAGGGCAGCGACGGACCCCCUGGGAAACCCGGACCACCUGGACCACCUGGUAUUCCAUUUAAUGAACGAAACGGCAUGAGCAGUUUAUAUAAAAUUAAGGGAGGUGUGAAUGUUCCCAGUUACCCAGGGCCACCCGGUCCUCCUGGCCCAAAAGGCGAUCCUGGCCCAGUGGGAGAGCCUGGUGCAAUGGGGUUGCCAGGAUUAGAAGGAUUUCCAGGUGUAAAGGGAGAUCGAGGCCCAGCAGGUCCCCCAGGAAUAGCAGGGAUGUCGGGAAAACCUGGUGCCCCAGGGCCUCCAGGAGUUCCAGGGGAACCGGGUGAGAGAGGACCUGUUGGAGAUAUAGGUUUCCCUGGACCAGAAGGACCCUCAGGAAAGCCAGGAAUAAAUGGAAAAGAUGGAAUACCAGGUGCUCAGGGCAUCAUGGGUAAGCCUGGAGACAGAGGCCCCAAAGGAGAACGUGGUGAUCAGGGGAUUCCAGGAGACAGAGGCUCACAAGGUGAACGGGGAAAACCAGGCCUUACAGGCAUGAAGGGGGCCAUCGGUCCUAUGGGUCCACCAGGAAACAAGGGCUCCAUGGGAUCCCCUGGCCACCAAGGCCCUCCAGGCUCUCCAGGCAUCCCUGGCAUUCCGGCUGAUGCAGUUUCAUUUGAAGAAAUAAAGAAGUAUAUUAAUCAAGAGGUCCUAAGGAUUUUUGAAGAGAGGAUGGCUGUAUUCCUAUCCCAGCUCAAGCUGCCAGCAGCAAUGUUGGCUGCCCAAGCUUAUGGGAGACCUGGGCCACCAGGGAAGGAUGGGUUGCCUGGGCCACCAGGAGACCCUGGACCCCAAGGCUACAGAGGACAGAAGGGAGAAAGAGGUGAACCUGGAAUUGGGCUGCCAGGGAGUCCAGGUCUUCCUGGGACUUCAGCUCUGGGUUUGCCAGGCUCACCAGGUGCCCCAGGCCCACAGGGCCCCCCAGGACCCAGUGGAAGAUGUAACCCAGAAGAUUGCCUCUAUCCUGUGUCUCAUGCCCAUCAGCGCACAGGUGGGAAUUGAACACACCUGAAGAAGACUUGGUUCCUGGUAACAUUUCCUUGCCACUGGAGCUCUCUUAAUACCGUCAAACCCUCAUCAUCUGUGGGUUGCUUUUUUUUUUUUUUUUUUUUUUUGGGAGUAAGCCAGGCAUUAAAAGCAACCGUUUGAAUCCUAUUCCUAUAGCAAUUGCAAAUCAGCAUUUUUUGAUUUUUCCCAAAUUCAUUCCAUAUGUUUUGCUUUACAAUUGCUAUGAUUUUUACUCAGAGUUUUAUAUGAAAUAUGCAAGUAAAUCUUAUCGUUAGUUCUUCUUCAAAAGGAAAUUGCAUCUUGUGACUUAGUAGACUGAUGAUGAUAUCCAUUUUGUAGACUCAUCAACAUGUGGUUGGCCUUUGAUUUCUGAAUUUUAAAGUUUCAGACUUAUCUUUUCCUUGGUGUUUAAAUUUACUAUCAUUGCUAAACAUCUCGUCAACUUUUUUGAUAUAGUGCAUUGCUCCUGUUGAAUGUUUUUUGACUACUUUUUAUAACUUAAGAAUUUUUAUACCAUCUACAUCUAUCCUACUUAUGCAGAAAAAUAGGCAAUAAGAACUUCAUUUUACAAUUUAUGUUUUCAAAAAAAAAAUGCAGGAAACUGUUUUAUCAGGGAGCCCAAACACCCAGCAUAGCCAACUACUGAAAUGAUUUUGUUAAUUCUGUAUAAUGAGCUCAAUUCAAAGCAAUCACCACUGGCAUGAAUAAGUACUGCAUGAAAAGGGAGUAUCAAAUUCCAGUUUUGUAUGAGUUCUGCAAAAAAAGCCUAAUAUUCUGUGGUCCCCUCACUCAGUCUCUCAUUUGGUAAACAGAAAGCUGUUUUCCCUACAAGGUGCUUGGUGGUGAAGCCACCAAGCUGUCUUUGGUACUCUUAAAGCUUCAGUGGCCUAGCAAGAUCUUUGGGCCCUUGUAUCCAUUAUCCUUAUGACCUCAUCACCCUCAGACUUUAAGACAAGAAGCCACCAUCAAAACAAAGGAUGGGAUACGUAUAGAAUGGACUCACUUGUCCUAGAAGAUGAAUGUGUAGUGUCAGCAAAUGCAUGUUAAGAAGGUGAAGCCCAAAAGCUCUUAAGGAGAAUUGUAUUUCUCCAGAAGCUGCAGCAAGAGGUACAGCUCAACAAAGGAAAACCACAGGACUGGAUAUGCAACUAGUGCUCAGACCAAAGAGUUCACACCCACUCUAAAACCAUGUCCUCUGAAAAGAAACAAAAAUACAGUGAUCAUCAAAUGCCUAAACAGUCUUUCUGUUGGUUAGCUGUACAUUCAUUGAGGAACUGUUGAUUGGCAGGCACUGAUUCUCUAGAACACUGGGCAUGAGGAUGUUGCAGAAAUCUAGAUGGUGGGUCCCACAGAUGUGAGAACAUGCUGCAAGAGCCUGCCAGCCACAGCAAUCAGGACUCACAGCUCUUCAAGGAGCAGUGCAGAUUUCAAUUUGGCUAAAACAGGAUGAUUGCUUUUGUCUGUUUACUGAAAAAUGAGUUUAGAAAGGCUAGCCCACUGACAUUGGAAAAAGCUGUGAACAGAGUUGUGUCUGAGGAAUGUGCCUAAUUUAAGGCAGGGUUUGUUCCAAUGCAUCCGUGAUUUGAACCGGUUUUCAUUAUAGAUUAAUGAACUGCUGGUCAGGUACUGUCUACAAUGGCUGUGCAUACCUAUAACAUUUUAGGUAUUUCAUAUUGAAUUAUGCUGUAUAUUUCAAUUCCAAGUUUAUUUAUUUUCCAAGGUUAUUUUAUUUAUUGUAAGCAUUUUGACAUUGAUUUUUUUUUUUUCGUUUUCUUUCUUGUGCAAUACCUACAAUGGUGCUGUGUUUUAAACUUACACAAUUGGGACAUACGUAUGUGUUUUCUUAGUAAAAUGGUAAUUUAUCCCGAAAAAGUGUACAUAGAUCUAAAAUUUGGUGCUAUGUGUAUAUCUUGAGCUUUUAAUUUGUUGAAUUUUCUAAACGCUUACAACUUAUCUGCCACUCAUAUUAAUUUACUUGAAUUUGUCAUAAAGCUAAAUAUUUUAUAUGUUUUCAAAGAUUAUUUUUUCAUAUUAAUAGGUUGUUUAUCUUUUUGCCUGUUUGCUAAUUUAAAAAUAUUUAUUUUAUCAUUUUAAUGUUUUCAUGGACUUUUUUGCUGAUGGUAAUCAACUUUUUUUGUUUUUUGGUUUUUGAGUUGUUCUUGUCAUAGACAUAAAAAGACAAUUCAUUUUCUUGUUUUAUUAACUCUGUUCAUUUUUAUUCUACAAAAUAUGUCAUGCAUUCUUUCUUAUGAAUUGUAUAUUUAGAAAUCUUUCUAAAUACCAUUAAGGCUUGACUGGUUAAUUCCUAUUUCAAGGAUUUGGAUUUAUUCAGGUAAUUUGAUGGGAUGGGGAAAUAUAAUAUUGUGUGAUGCAUAUUACAAAGUGGACUUGUCACAAUGACACAAACUCAUUUUUUGUAACUGGGAAAUAUGACUAAAUUUGACGUAACUAGAGAAACAAGGCUGUAUCCACAUGGUACAAGCCUUUCUCACCCUACUCUAUUAUUUACCUUCAGAUACUUUUUCCUGCCUCAGCUCUGUACACAUGAUAUGCAACAAAGGGCAGCAAGAAAUGCUGGGUCCACCUAAUUUAACACAAAAUGAAGUUGAGAUUCGGCAGUUGCCCAAUUCCUUUAAUAAAAAGAAACUAAAUAAUUUGGGCCCCAAAGUAGGGUGGGAAGUUUUCCUCUAAAUGACUUGAUGGUUGCCAAAUCCCUUGCACCAUUUUAUUCCAUUCCAAAACAUGUGUUUAUUUCCACAUAGAUGUUAAUGAUGUUCAAAGCAGGGGAGAAGAAUUAUUCAAUUUCAUGAAUAACUCUUGUUUGCACUCCAGAAAACAACAUACAUGUUUAAAUACAAAAUAAUUAUGGGCCAUGACGACGAUUAAUAUUAAAACUGUGAUUUCCAUAUACAAGUAUGUUUGAGUUCCAAUCUUACAUUUUAUACCAAGUUCAAAACACUUUCAGAUAGAAGUCUUUCUAUGCAAAGAUUAAAGUAUGACUUCAAUUCAUAUUUAUGGCCUUUGGAAUCCAAAGAAAAACAGAAGAAUAAUUCAUGGAUUUGUUCAUUGUUCUUUCCAACUGAAGGCAGUAACCAUUACUUCUAACCGUAACACAAACACAGCAAGUUUUAACCUUUUAAACUUUUCACUUUGUGAGCAAAGUAACCCCAUAAGUUUAUUUCCCUAUUUCAUGGUAUUGUUUAAACUUUAAAAUUUUAGUCACUUAAAGAACUUAAGCAAUUAUAUUAAAAUACGUUGUCUGUGAAAAUUAUCAUUUGAUAUUUGGCUUAUAAAGUAAUUUUUAUGAAUCUGUUUUAUGAGUUAGGUAAGAUUUAGCCUUUCUGCAGUCUGUCUCAUCUGUUGGGAACCUGUGAUAUACCUCCAUUUGUCCACAAGAUGGUGUUUAAAACAAUUUGUUCAGAAGAACUGAGCAAACUAACAGAAAUACAAGGCUACGAACAGUUUAGUGGACAACUAAAUCAGACUCUUGCCUUUGCACUUUUUUUUAACUUUUGUAGAUAAUUUUUGUUAAUUUGUUUUGUUAAUUUAUGUUUUUCCUAAUUUUAAGCAUCUUUAUGAAACAGGCACAGUACCCUUUGGUUUGUUGACUGUUUUGAUUUUAUUUCUUUGGUGGAUAUAUAUGUACUUAUACACUUAGUUAACAUGCAGAUUAACUAGUCAUAACUGUUUAUACACCACUCUCAUAUUUUAGUGAUCAAUAUGAAGACAGCUAAAUAAUUAUCCUACUUUUUAGACAGGACAGAUACUCUCAACAGACAAGAAAAAAGAUUUAGCUUAUCACAAGAAGCAGACAAUUUAUAAAACUACACAAUGUCUAAACUCUAUGUUGCUCAGUGUACUUAAAAUUUUACAGUUAUAUUUGUAUAACGUUUAUAUUUUUCUAGAAUACAUCACUAUUUACAAAAGUACAAUUAGAAACACUGUUUUUUUUAAGUACCGUUUUUAUUUUCAUAACACUAAUAAUACACUGGGAUUGAGAAUUUCUGUUAAGUGUUUUGCUGACGUUGUUUUAAUGAAUACUCAAAAAAGCUUUGCAGAUUUGUCCAUUGCUCUUGUUCUUAAAUUAUUUUUCAUACUUGUCUGUAUCCACCUUCUGAAGACACACAAGUGUUUACUGUCGCAGUUUCCCAGCGUUAUUUCUUAAUACUUGAGUGUUGACACAUUUUUGUACCAUCCCCCUUUUGUACCAUCUCUGCUCACAAAGAUUAUAUGCAGGCUUUGAAGAGGAGGAGAUGCAGAAGAUAAUUGAAUUUGUAUCUUGUAUGCCUAUGUAAUUCAAAGUGACUUAGUCCAUUGAAUUGUGUUCAUUUAUUAGUUGGCUGGUUAAGAUAGCAUUAAUUAUCUUAAAUUUAUUCAACUACUAAAAGUCUCAGGCAAUAGGACAGAUGAGUGUCAUCAUUUUUAUUGUGUGGCAUACUUGGAGCUAUAAUCCAAACGUUUUACUCAACAAAAUAAUGCUAGAGUAACUGAUCAAUUUGGUUAAAUUGAAUGAAGAACCAAGUGAACACAGAGAAAACUUAUUCGGACAAGUAGACCCAGCACAGCAAAAAUUUGUCUGAAAGAUAAGACAAGCUUAUAAGACCAAAGCUAAGUCUAAGAAAAUCUAAAUGGAAAAAAAAUUGCGUGUUCAGAUCCAAUAGUGAGUGAUGUGGUACAACUGGAGGAGUUAGCUACUUGCUUCAUGAAUUUGUCAAAAGUGAAUACUAAUAAAGUGGGAGGCUUCACUAAAUGAGGGGGUAAAUAAGAUUUAAGUUUAUCAGAAGUGUGUGUAUUGUGUGACCAUACUAAGCUUCUGGGUGUAAGUAAAGAUGCUGGCUAUUUUACAACUUUUUAUUGUAUUGUGUUAUGCAAAGUACAUUUUGGAGAUAAAUGUUUUUCAGCACAUUAAUGUCUUUAAAUUCAGGUUGUAUUGGGUGUAUUUUACAACUAUUUAUUUUUAAAUAACAUUUAGGGUGUGUUUUCCCCCAUUUUGUUUGUUCUCUAUCUUACCUCAUCAAACUCUUUACGAUUUAAUUGAAUAUACUCAUGUUAAGUGCAAUGGCAUUAGUUUUAUUCAAAAUCCCACAUGGGCAUAAUGCUUUGAGGCCUUGAUUCCUACAUGUUCAUUAUGCAUAAUGAGCUUGUCACCUAUCUCAGCAAUAAAGGUUCUGACCCUAUGUCAGGGAAA